GCCAUUUUGGAGGGGCCGCGGGAGACGUGGUGCCGCUGCGGGCUCGCUCUGCCGUGCGCUAGGCUUGGUGGGAAGGCCUGUUCUCGAGUCCGCGCUUUUCGUCACCGCCAUGUCGGGAGGUGGUGUGAUUCGUGGCCCCGCAGGGAACAACGAUUGCCGCAUCUACGUGGGUAACUUACCUCCAGACAUCCGAACCAAGGACAUUGAGGACGUGUUCUACAAAUACGGCGCUAUCCGCGACAUCGACCUCAAGAAUCGCCGCGGGGGACCGCCCUUCGCCUUCGUUGAGUUCGAGGACCCGCGAGACGCGGAAGACGCGGUGUAUGGUCGCGACGGCUAUGAUUACGAUGGGUACCGUCUGCGGGUGGAGUUUCCUCGAAGCGGCCGUGGAACAGGCCGAGGCGGCGGCGGGGGUGGAGGUGGCGGAGCUCCCCGAGGUCGCUAUGGCCCCCCAUCCAGGCGGUCUGAAAACAGAGUGGUUGUCUCUGGACUGCCUCCAAGUGGAAGUUGGCAGGAUUUAAAGGAUCACAUGCGUGAAGCAGGUGAUGUAUGUUAUGCUGAUGUUUACCGAGAUGGCACUGGUGUCGUGGAGUUUGUACGGAAAGAAGAUAUGACCUAUGCAGUUCGAAAACUGGAUAACACUAAGUUUAGAUCUCAUGAGGGAGAAACUGCCUACAUCCGGGUUAAAGUUGAUGGGCCCAGAAGUCCAAGUUAUGGAAGAUCUCGAUCUCGAAGCCGUAGUCGUAGCAGAAGCCGUAGCAGAAGCAACAGCAGGAGUCGCAGUUACUCCCCAAGGAGAAGCAGAGGAUCACCACGCUAUUCUCCCCGUCAUAGCAGAUCUCGCUCUCGUACAUAAGAUGAUUGGUGACACUUUUUGUAGAACCCAUGUUGUAUACAGUUUUCCUUUAUUCAGUACAAUCUUUUCAUUUUUUAAUUCAAACUGUUUUGUUCAGAAUGGGCUAAAGUGUUGAAUUGCAUUCUUGUAAUAUCCCCUUGCUCCUAACAUCUACAUUCCCUUCGUGUCUUUGAUAAAUUGUAUUUUAAGUGAUGUCAUAGACAGGAUUGUUUAAAUUUAGUUAACUCCAUACUCUUCAGACUGUGAUAUUGUGUAAAUGUCUAUCUGCCCUGGUUUGUGUGAACUGGGAUGUUGGGGGUGUUUGUGGUUAUCUUACCUGGGGAAGUUCUUAUGUUUAUCUUGCUUUUCAUGUGUCUUUCUGUAGACAUAUCUGAAGAGAUGGAUUAAGAAUGCUUUGGAUUAAGGAUUGUGGAGCACAUUUCAAUCAUUUUAGGAUUGUCAAAAGGAGGAUUGAGGAGGAUCAGAUCAAUAAUGGAGGCAAUGGUAUGACUCCAAGUGCUAUUGUCACAGAUGAAAUUGGCAGUAUUGACCUUAUACUAAAAGGCAGGGGUUAAAAAUGAUUAUAUACAUUUUCCUUAAAACACUUGCAAACAUUUUAUUCAGUUGUCUUUAGCUACAAUUGCUUUGCUUUUUAAACCUUGGCAAUUGUGGCAAAAUUAUAUUGCCCAUUUUGUAGCAACUUAUUUUGCUCCCUUCCCCCCAUUUUUGUUUUAAUAGGGACUAAUGUGGGAAGAACUGGCUAAUUUGUCACAGUGCUUAGUUACAACUGUUAAUGUGUGACCUGCUGUUGGUGUACAUGUGGGUACAGGGUGUUUUUAAAUCCAACAAGAUAGAGUAUAAUAUCAAUACUGCUAAAUCUGCAUGUCCUCUGUGUGACUGAUAGAGCGUUGCUAUUUCAUUUUUUUAAGACAAAAUGAAAGCAAAAUAUAGAGUUCCAAUGUAUUGGUGUAGAUAAUCUAGUUGGGAAUACUUUUAAGUCUCACCUUCCCCUUUAAACUAAUAUUCAUAAUUGGUUCAUAUGUUUAAAAGACUUUAAUUUACAAAUUAAAUUGCAAAUGGGAGCAUUAGAUUUAGUUUUAGACUUAGGUGGGUAGCAAUGCCAGUAAACUUAAAUUACGUAACUUCUUGCAACCACGAAACCUGUAAUACGCUGUACAGUAACAAGUGUUGGCAUUAUCAGUUGAACUGUAAAUACAAAAUGCUUCUUCCAAUUAGUCUCUAUGAUGAUUAAGUUUCUAAAAUUUAUCUGAACACCAUUCAGAAACUUGUUUUGGGGAAUUUGAUAGUUAUUGAUGUGCAUCUGUUAAACUGAUGACAGACAUAACUCAUCAUUCCCCAGAAACCUUUUUUGAUUACAGUAUCUAACAUUUUGCCUCCUCUUUUUUGGUUUUGCUGGUUAUAAAGGUUUGGAUUGGAGAGGGCUCACUGGAUCCCAAUCCUUGGAGCUGGAUCAUUGGAUUCAAAUCAUAAUGUGGAUAGGAUAGGGAGGAUGAAUUACCAGGAUUCAUGGAGCGGGAUCAGAUUACCAGGAACAUAGGAGUGGAUUCCUGCCCCAACCAAACCGCAUUCGUGUGGAUUUUUUUAUUCAACUUAAUUGGCUAUUCCAAAGAUUUUUUUUUUCCUAUUUUUGACGAUUGGAGCCCUUAAGAUGCACGAUGGAAUUGUGUUUUGCGUUUUUUGGUAAAAGGAGCAAAGCGAGGACCUGGAGAUAAACGCUGGAGCAAUCUCCUUGGAAGGAUUCAGCACGAGUAGAUGGUAAACAUUUAAAGGGGAAAGGGGGGGUUUGUUUAAAAUAGUAAAUCAGUAAGUCACUUCUAAAUUUAAAGAAAACAAAAUUGGAGUUGAAGAAUAAGUAGGUUUCCAAUUGGCUAUUGCCGUUUUCUUUGAAAAAAUAAACAUUUUUUAAAAAACUAUGCAUGGUUGUCCUUUUUCCUCUUCAUGUAAGAUUCUAACUGGGUCUAUCAGUUAAUCUUUAAAUUGUUAAGUAAGAUAAGAUUUUGACUCUUGUGUUAAUGUGUUAGCAAAUUAAAAGUUCUUAAAAGGCAAUCUAAUGGUAUUAGCCAUCUUUUAUUGUUAAUUGUAAAAGUCUUCAGGGGAAAGCAAAAGGGGAGAAUAAGGCAUUUGUGUAUGUAACUUGGUAAAUGACGGUGGGGGAUGGAUCUAGCAUCUGAAAGAUAAGCUUCUCUACUUUGUUAUAAAGUGGUUAAAAAACUAUAGAUGCUGCUUAUUUUCUGGUGGUCAUAGACAACAUAGGCUUUUGUGCAAAAUUGGUUGAUGGCUACUAAUGUUCACUUGGAGAUAGCUUUUGAUAUUCUCAAUGAAACUCAUCUCAAAAAAAGGUAAGUAUUAAAUGUUAACAUCAGCACAGAUGUAUUAGAACUGUUUUUUGUUUUUGAGACAGAGUCUCGCUCUGUUCUCCAGACUGGAGGGCAGUGGUGUGAUCUAGGCUCACUGCAACCUCCACCCCUGGAUUUGAGUGAUUCUCGUGCCUCAGUCUCCCAAGUAGCUGAGACUACAAGUGUGUGCCACCCUUGCCCGGCUAAUUUUGUAUUUUUAGUAGAGAUGUGGUUUCUCUGUGUUACCCAGGCUGGUCCCAAAACUCCUGGCCUCAAGUGAUCUGCCUGCCUUGGCCUCCCAAAGUGUUAGGAUUACAGGUGUGAGCCACCAUGCUCAGCCUGUAGAACUUUUAACCCAAGUCUCAUUUCUUUUUUGAAAGGGAAGAGUGCACAAGAUUAACUGCUUCUUUGGAUGAAUCAUUGUUAAUAAAAAGCUGGGCAUUUAGAAUUUUGCCUUAUAAGCCCUUCUCCAACCAUAAGAUUAUUUUGUACCAAAAACUUUGGUGUUCUCUACCAAAGCAGUUAAAAACUUUUAGCCUGCUACUUCUUGUAUUUGUCUACUGACAGCCCCUUGGUACUAUUUAGGUUGGGGGAGGGGACCUAAAAUAAAUAGACUUUAACAUUUCCCUUGGGUGCUAAUCAUAGUUGGAAGUUGAAUUUAAGGUGAUUAUUUGGGUGACAAUUAAAAACCUAAGGAAAACCAGAAAUCUUGGUAGUGGAAGAAAUGUGUAAGGUCACCCCAAUCGGUAGAUUUUAAUGAACGUUGUGGAAUGUUGGGAAGAGGGGAUGUUAAGUUGAAUGCAGAAUUUCACUAAGUACUUAGUGUAAGUUUAAGGAUGUAGCUCUUUUUAUCUAAGAAUUCAAUGUAAUGGCCAAAAGGCAGAUUUACUGUUUAAAAAUUUGAAUAAUUUUACAUGACAUUCUUGAAAUUCUAAGAAGUUUUAUGUGUAGAACAUUUUAAAAAUUCAUCAGAUUAUUAAAGGGAAAAUAAAUGAUUAAUGAUAAUUUUGGAAGGUUAAUGUGAGCUAGACUUAAGUAAACUUUGGUUCAUUUGUGUUCAUUGAAUGUUUUGGAAAUGACCAAAAAAUGUAAAUGGCCUUCACUCAAGUUUGAGUGUUUAAAGUUGAAAGAUGUGCUCUACUAAAAGUUAUAGUAAUUCUAACCUCACAUUGAAAUGAGACAGUAUUCCUUGUUAUACAGGCUGAAUUUGAAGAUUAGAGAGGAUCUAAUGUUUACUUAGGUAAAGGGGCAUAGGUUUUGUAGUUAAGAUGACCAGACAGCUAAAAGCUGUGAUGGGAAGUAUGGACUGCUCCUAUUUAUAGUCUCAGAAAAUGGACCUUUAGGUCUCUAUCCGUAUUGGCAAUUAUUAGAAGAAAGUUACACCCUUUUGAAACUACAAAAGCUGUCUUGGAAUUUCCCCCUCUUCUCCCUAUUUAUGUCCCCUUAGAAUAUUUUAGGGAGCCUAUAAUUAUUUUCUAACCAAGGAAAAACUUAAGUCUCUUUAAGAAGCAAUUACUUUUCAUAACAUCAGAUUGAAUAACCCACCUUGCUGUUCAGCCCACAUCCUACUGGAAACAAAAGGUAAGAAACCCAUUUUCUGGUUCUUGAUUGUUUGGGUCUGAAUUUUGUUUUUAAAACUAAGCUAAGUUUAAUGUUUUUUAAAAUGCUGUUUGGAAUAUGAAUAGAUUCCCCGUAAAAUGAUUUUUCCUAAGUUUUAUGCUUUAGUAAAUAUUCAGUGCUCACGUCUGUGCAUCAUAGUGCUUGCGUUUAAUAUGAUUUAUUGUAGAAUCUCAACUUUUCUUGGUGUUUGUUGUCUUUGAAACAUUGUCUUGGUCAUUAGGGCUGGUGUUUUCACAUUUCUGUGGUCAAGGUGGAUUUCUUAUGUGUGCCUUUUUGCUUACUUUGUAUAUGAAUUUUGUAAUUUAAAUUGCAAGUAAGUUAUAUAUAUGUAUUUACCAUAAAUAGUAUUAAAAGAUGAGAAACUGUUAGACUGAAGUUCUGUUGUAACAUAACCAUUAUUUCCAUCACAGUAUGAAGACUGCAAACGCAGAAAACAGAUUACAGUCUCUUAUCCAUUUUUUGAAAUCCAAAAACUACGAAAACAAAAGAUUUUCUGUUGUUGAGCUAAUUAAAUGUGAACCCUGACCAGAAUUGCUGCCUUCAUUUUGCACUUAGUGUGACUAAACUGUUUCCUGUUGAACUUCAUUAUUCAUUGCACAGUUGCCACAGACUUUGCUGAGGGUUUUAUGUAAUACAGGGUAUAUAUGUACCUCAUAAAGUGCAUACAGCUCUGAAUCCCAGAUAUGUCUGUCUCCAAAGAGUUCAUAUAAGGGAUUGUAGGAACUGUACUAGCAUACACAGGCCUAAUGCUUUUGUCUGUAACUGGGGUGUCUUGACUGAAAAACCUGUUAUUGUGAAUCCUUUGUUGAUUGAAUUUUAAGUUCCCCCAUCUUUUUAGGCUGAAGCAGCCACAAGAAAAAAAGGUAUGGCCCACAUUUCUUUACAUUCUGUUGUAAUAGUGGACUCAACAAUUAUAUCCCAUUGAAGCAAAUACUCAGGCAUCCUAGAGUGUACAAUACAACAUUCUUUUGAGUUAUUGUUUCUGUAUCAGUACUUAAAGGAACAUUGACCAAUUAGAUCCUAUAGGAAAAGCUGGGAUUGGCAUGAAGUAAAGAGAUUAUCAGGAAACAUCUGUUCAUUAUGUCUAUCGUGAUUGUCUAUUGAAUGAAUAGUAAUGCUGCCAAAAGUAACUUGCUUUAAACAAACCCCAAGAGAUUAUAGUAUACUUAAACCAGUACUUAUUCCUGUUAUUGAGACCUUCACGGUGCUUCUUGGUAGCUUUGAAAGCUAAUGCCUAACAACCCUGAGGGUUCUUGUGAGCUUGUAGUGAUUAAAGGAAGGAUUUUUUAAUUAUUAUAAAAAUCACUCCGUGCUUCAUUAAUGCACAGAAUAAAAAUUGAAUAAAUGACUCUGUCAUAUAGAAGUUAAUUUAGGCAAAUAUAACAUUUGUAAUUUACAACAUUUUAAUAGGUGCUAGGCUGGGAUUUCAGGGGGUGAAAAGUCAUUCAUGACUUUUCAUAAGAAGUUUACUGUUUAGGUAAGCAAAACAACACUUAGUUCAGCUUGAUACUCAAGCAUCGGGUUAAAAAGCAUCAGACUUCUGUUACCAGACAACUUAUAAGUGCCAACUAUUGGUAGAACUGUGGACAUGAAGAUAGUGGAAACAGCUUCUCUAGGAUGCUAUACUCAUCUCCACCAAAUGCACUUUGAACAAAAACAACUUGUAGAAAUAGGUCUUAAUUUUUUUUGUUUGUUUGUUUGGUUUUUUUACAACAUGCUGUACUGCUCUCCAUUGGUAAGUGCUAGGGAAAAUCACUUAGCCACUAGAGGGAGCUAUAACACAAAAUUAAGCAGGAAAUAAUCCCCAUUAUAGAUACAUAGAACAAAGUAGAGACCAGCUAACUACCUUGAUCCUCUGUAUCAGCUCUAAAGUUAGAUGGUUUGGGUAAGUUUUCUUGCAACUUUACCUUUGUCUUCCCAUCUUUUGUGUAAAAUUCUUCCCCUUUUCAGCUUUUGCAUCCAUUUAGGUUUUCAGAGUUUACCUUACAGGCACUCAUUUUGUAACAAAUCUAGGUUCUGGGACUAAGAAAAUACUGAAGACAUAAGUCUGCUUGUUUUUCUGCCUACCUUGUACAUCAGGUAUGGAAUAAUAAGGCCAUGAAUGUGAGAAUUGGGAACAGGAGUUAGGUGUGCUGGGGAAAACUAGACAUAACAAUUUGGUUAUGAACUAGAAGAAAUGAAUAUGCUUUUAGAGACCUGCAGUUUGCUUUUAUGGAGUGACAGUUUCAGGUGUGAUGAUCUUCUCAGUAUUACUAAGAGGUUCUUAAAGUUUGUCUUAAAAUCCUACUUAUGUGUCAGCUUAGCUGUUUUCUAUUUUCUAGGCCUCACUUAAGUAGCAGGUUGUCUUGUGAUCAAAAAGUCAGUAGACACAGUAGUUAAUGCCAUAUUAACAGCUGAAAAUUACUGAAAAUUUAACACUUUUAGUAUCUGUCAUUCCCAUCACCGCUUUCUCCCCAGGUUUCUUUUAUAAAAAAUGGAAAGGACACAAACUUGUCUCCUGUUUACAGUAUAAAUUGUCAUUGAGAAUACUAAACCUUUUAGGCCCAUAUGAUGGGAUUUAGUCAUCCAGAAGACAGGUGUGGGACAACUGGCCUUAAAAUGUUAAUUUUAGAAAAUCAGUCUGUUUCAAAGAAUAAAGCACUAAAAGUGGACAAAGUGGACUUCUUGUGGGGGGAAAAGUAAUCAAGUUUACACAGUAGAGAUUUCCCUGCCUGCUAAGGUAACACUAAGUAGCAAGGAAAGCUACAGAAGGUAGUUACUGUUAACUAGUAGUCUUGCUGCAAAUUGGAUUGACAGCUGAAAGGGCACUAACUAGAUUGAAGCCUGUCUUUAAUCCUGUAAAUGUUAGCUCUGGUGUCCCUUUGAUAAUUUUUAAAUAACUUUUGAAGAUGCACUCUGAAGCCACAAAUUAGGCAAAUGAAAAUUCAGAAUUCUCCUUGUAGAAAGAAAAGUGCUAAACCUGGAGAUUGUAAAGUGCUAAGAAAAACCAUGGUAGAAUUGUUCCCUCAGGUGCUGUGUAUUAGAGGAGGAGUCUUUAUAUGUCAUUUUGGGAUAAGCUUUCAACAAUUAUUAAGGCUUAAUACAUAAGAUUAUAGGAUCAGUCAAGCAAAAGGGAAGGUAUAACCUUUAGAUAGGACUGGGAAGUGCUGGGUGAAUGUCUUCUACCCUUAACGGUGGUAGAAAUUUGAACUAUAAAAUAACACCAAGAGUGACAUUCACAUUUUUUUUGUCUUUGUUUUUGACACAGGGUCUCACUCUGUCACCCAGGCUGGAGUGUAGUGGCACAAUCUCGGCUCACUGCAACCUCCGCCUCCCGGGUUCAAGCGAUUCUCCUGCCUCCCAAGUAGCUGGUAUUACAGGUGCCCAUCACCACACCUGGCUAAUUUUUGUAUUUUUCAUAGAGACAGGGUUUCACUAUGUUGGCUCAGCUGGUCUCUGAACUUCUGAUCUCAAGUGAUCCGCCCGCCUCGGCCUCCCAAAGUGCUGGGAAUACAGGUGUGAGCCAGCGCACCUGGCUGACAUCCACAACUUAAGGCUAGAAAUGUAAAAUGUUGGUUCGCAGUGUAACAAGCACAUUCCAAAGAAAACUCAAAUGGCUCCUUUGUACUCUAAAAAUAGUAAAUUUGCAGCAAGGUGAUAGUCAAGUUCUGUGUCUUCAGGGUGCCACCGCAUCUAUGAUUUAGAUUAACCUAGAGAUGUGUUUACUUGCCAAAUAGAGUUCUUCAAGAUGCUGUUUGGAUUUGUCUUCCCAUCUCCAGUUGCCAUAUCAGCAUUUUUGUCUGUACCCAAAUUCAUAUUACUGAAGUGUUAAAGCUGGUUUCAGUGACUCCAGAUCCUUAAAACAUGUCACUCCCUUAAUAUGAGUUAACAAUGGGUUAUAUUCUACCUUUCCAAUUUAUCCUGUUCUCAAUCACAUCUUCCCCUACCCUGGUUGAUUUGGUAAAUACAUGUAUUUUUUAACUCUACAGACCCAGGAACUGAAUAUAUUUAUAUUUCCCAAUGAGCUAAAUGCAGUGCUGACAGUUUUAAUAUUGAUGGGCGAGAUGGGAAGAAUUUAGUAUUCCCUAAAAGCAAAGCACUGUAGAAGUCUGUUUCACAAGCUAUUCGUUAACUGGGUGGAUUAUUGGAGAAGGUAUUUUAAUACUAAUAACUCCUCAGAUGUGAAGCCAGAAAAUUUGAAUUAAUCUAAAUGCUAGCCUAAGUCCAAGUAUAAUUGGAUAAGUAAAUGUUGCUCCCAGAAUUGGUCUUGCAAAGUAAGACCAAUUGUAAGACCAAAGUAAGUGGUUUUGAUGUAAGCUGUGCACACUUUCAGUACAGAUCACCAAGAAUUGAUGACAUUGUCUCCAAAAAGACUAAAUAGUUGCCUCCUAGGUAUCCUUUUUCAGUCAUUCUCUUUUAAGCUUCUUACAGAGGAAGCUUUAAGUUGCCUCAGAAUUUAGUGGUAUUGCCUCAAUGAGAAUUCCUGCAUAUUUCUCUUUGGGAUGGAAUCAUUUUGGUUGUUUUUUUGUUGUUGGUAACUAUUCAUAAAGAGAUUAAUACAUAACGAUGUAUUGUGAAGAGACUAGAUAGCAUGUAUAUUAUUCCUUGGGUUGGGAGUCUUAAGCAUUAACUUUAGGACCCUGACCCUGGUCUUUAGGUUUAUAGGAUCAGCUAGCUUAAACAAUUCUCUCAAAACCAAGAGACCCAGCAUCCAUACAUUUUAACACCCCACAUCAUAAAUCCCAUAAGCAGCCCCAUUCCUUUUGCCAUUAAAAAUCUCACCCCUUCAUGAUCACACCUAAUGACUGAAGCAUUCUUGAACUAAUUGCGUUGUUUCUUAUUUGCUUUUCUUCAUGUUUUAAAAAGUGCUAUAUGUGCAGGUGGACAUGUUGCCCUUAAGCUGUUCUCUAGUUUAAUGUGUAUGCUUUGUUUUCUUCAGCUACAUAGUAAACUGAGAGCAAAGGCUGUUUUUUUUUUUUUUUUUUUUAAGACAGUGUCUUGCACUGUCACCUGGGCUGGAGUGCAGUGGCGCAGUCUCGGCUCACUGCAACCUCCACCUCCUGGGUUCAAGCGAUUCUCCUGCCUCAGCCUCCCAAGUAGCAGGGAUUACAGGCACCUGCCACCACACCUAGCUAAUUUUUUGUAUUUUUAGUAGAGACAGGGUUUCACUAUGUUGGCCAGGCUGGUCUCAAACUCCUGACCUCGUGAUCUGCCCGCUUCGGCCUCCCAAAGUGCUGGGAUUACAGGCAUAAGCCACCGCGCCCGGCUCCCCAAAGUCUUAUGUUUUAAACUUUUUGACAUUUCUUCUAAGAUGUCCAGAAUGCUAGUACCUGCACCUUAAUAAAUGUUUGUGAAUAAAUACAUUAUUGAAAUCUUAGGCAGGUGUGCCACAUAGCUUAAAUCUGAGACACUGUGUUCUUUAGUCAGAUCAUGCAUAUUCUUAGAAUAGUAACCUCAAAGGUUUAUACCCUUGCUACCUUUUUUAUAUUUUUUGUAGAGACAGGGUCUUGCUCUGUUUCUCAGACUUUUUGAACUCCUGGGCUUAAGCAGGCCUCCCACCUUGGCUUCCUAAAGUGCUGGGAUUACAGAUAUGAGCCACUGCGCCCAGUCCUGAUACUGUGGCUCAUUUUAAUUCUCACGUAGUAUUUAGUUUCAUUUUGCAGUUUGAAGAAAUAGGCCCAGAGAUGUUAAAGGGGCAGGCCCAGAACUUGAAUCCAGAUCUUGUGGUGAGAAAUUCUUGUUUUACUAUCACGUUGCUUUUUAAAGCCAGCCUGCUUUUUCCAGUUGGGAGGCCUCGGGGAGAAAAGUCUGACCCAAGUGAGAAACACCUGUAAUAUCUACCAGAUGCCAGCAGGGUGUCCCAUGGUGCUGUCUUUGAUCCAUGUUCUUACCCUGUGUGCUGAGGGUUGUUCUAGAGUAGGACUACAUCUAGUCACAGUGGCCAUGUUCCAGAGCCUGGCAGCAAGAAAGAGGGAUGCCUAGCUCCUUGGCUUUCCAGUGUGCAGUGCACAGCCAGCUCUCUCAGAGAAGCCCUGGCCCUCUUUUGACCCCUACUAUUGAGGCUGGCCCCACAGGAGGACAGCUGGUCACACAGUGGCUGGGGCCUGGCUAGCCACUCAAUAACUACACAGCAGCCCCACAAAAAAAUCAUAGAAAAGAACCUGUGAAAGGGUAAAUGUUUAAAACAUCUGCAUUUGUGUUGAUAGCUGAGUAUACACUUAAAUUUGUAUUAGUAACAGAUCCACAAAAAUGAACCACUCUAGGAAUUUUAAGUUUUAAAAGCCAAUGUGUGGUAACUUCCAGUUUCCAAUAAAAAUGUUUGCAUUACACUUAGCCUACACAUACUAUCUCUUAGGUAUCAGUUUUUGUAUUCAGCAACCCUAGUUGGUAAUCUACAGUGUCAAAACUAUCACUUAUAUGAAAACAAAUGAGCAAAUAGCCCUUUAAAAAUUUCCUUUCCCAGUGCUCGUUACGCACUUUGUACAAAUGUCUGUAACUGUUUUAUAAUUAUUUCUUUGCAAGGCUUGGUUUCUUCAGUAGAGAAGAUUCUUAGAAGUAUCCCCAGUGACAGUACAGCUCCUGGCAUUUAGUAGGUGCUCAGUAAUUAUUUUACUGAAAUACUCAUGCUUCCAUAAUAGUUCUGGGAUAAUUCUAAACACAAGCCAUUUUUCUAAGGAGAGUCCACAUUAGAGAGGUCUUUGUUUUGUAUUCAAGAUGAUUAAAAUUAUGAACUGGGAAGUUAGUCCCUGGGGUGUCCUGGCUGGCCUUUGGAAAUCUUCACUACAUCUUUCUGGGUUGGAAUUCUCACCACAGCCUGAACGUGGGGCUGUAUCUGAGCUGUCUCUGAGUGCUGUCCAUUUGAUAUAUCGAGUACUGGGUGUUUACCAGGGCUCUUCAAGCCACUGGGAGAAACAGCUAAAGAGUAACCUACUGAUUUGAGAUGUGGAUUUGUGCCCCAUCCCUUUCUCCUUGUUUCCCACAGGAGUUUUAUCUCAAACUCCUAAGCCAUUUUUAAGGAGAUCACUGGAACAAACUCCAAACCUACCCUCUAAUAGUCAAGUUUACCUGAAUUUUCUCAGUUCUCUCGGGAGAAGACUAAUCACACAUUGUAGUACCAACUUGGACUCUUCAUGUGCUUUUCUUAACUGAUUAGAGUUAACACCUCAGCUAAAGUGUAUAGAACAUACAUGGGGCUUCAUCAGGCUUCAGAAUCAGUUUCACUAGAUGUGCUAUGUAGGAGGCCACGGAAAAAUUACUGUAGUAGUAAAAGUUAUCAGUUCUGAUGUAAACAAUCAUUUUGUCCCAUAUUAUAAAUAAAUUGGCCUGAAAAUAUCUUUUCAUAUGUGAGGAAUAAGUAUAUGAUGCCUUUCUCCUUUAAAGUAUGAACUGCUAAAAGACAGGGAUAACGUGUAUUCUGUAUUCCAGCAGCCACAGUGUGUUUCUGGUCUUUGUACCAGGUGCUCAGGAAGUGUUUUCACUGGCUUGGGUUGACUACUUGCCAUCUGCUCUCUGAGCAUUCAUUUCUGAAUGAAAGGGGAGAAAGUGAAAGGAGAGGUGGGAAGAAAGAGGAAGCUGCAGAAAUACGAGGAAACAGCUGGAGGAGGGAGGUGAAGUUGAGGAGGUAAGGUCAGUAAAACAAAAAGCUAGCAGAGGGCAGGGUCAGGCCCUUGGGGUAGAGGGCUAAUUAACUUCUGUCAGCUAGUUGAAUAGAGCCUUGUGUGCUUUGUUAGAGACCAAAGGUACUUCAAAGGAAAAAAAUCUAGAUUCUUCCCUGUGUACCUUAAUAAUUGUUCAUCAGGUCAAAAUCUAUCCUGUCCUCUAGGAAUUCUGGUCUUCCCUCAGGCCUAGCAGAGAGCUUUCUGCCACUACUCAGGCAACCAAGGGUGAAGUGCUUCAAGUAGUAUUUGUGGACAGCAGCAGGUAAGCUUGAUGUGUUAUUCACAGCUUAAAGAGUAGAUGCUGAGUACAGCUGUUGUCCAUGUGUAGAGCUUUUAAUAACCAGCGCAGCAGGCCCCUUCACCUGCUUUUAUGCCUGGACCAGAUGACUGAAUGUAGAACUUUAGGCACUUUUUUUUUUUUUUGAGACGGAGUCUCGGUUUGUUGCCCAGGCUGGAGUGCAGUGGCGCAAUCUCGGCUCACUGCAAGCUCUGCCCCCCGGGUUCACGCCAUUCUCUUGCCUCAGCCUCCCAAGUAGCUGGGACUACAGACUCCCACCACCAUGCCCGGCUAAUUUUUAUAUUUUUUAGUAGAGACAGGGUUUCACCGUGUUAGCCAGGAUGGUCUCAAUCUCCUGACCUGGUGAUCCACCUGCCUUGGCCUCCCAAAGUGCUGGGAUUACAGGUGUGAGCCACCAGAUCGGCCCUUUAGGCACUUUCUACUUCUCAAGGUCAAGAAACAUCCUUUAAAAAGUUAAUUCCCUUUUCUGGAGCCUAAGCCAGAUCUUAUCUAGGCCUUGUGUUGCCAUCUGUUAGCAUUGAUUUCUGGAAUGGAGCAGCUUUCUCAAAGUUUGGUCUUGCUAGUCAUGAGGUCAUGUCAGUGUCUUAGGUCACUGCUGCUCACCUUCCUUACCCAGGGAGUAUACUGCAUAGGUUUCUGAACACCUGUUUUCAUUAUUCACUGUUCCUCUCACUGCCAAGAAUGGAGGGACCCUCAGUUGAAGAUCAAAUUGACUCUGAAGAAAAACUGGAGAUGUUUCUCUUGGAGUUUGGAUAGAGUAUUCACUUGAUAACAUGUUUUUCCCCUGCCUUGCUCUUCACAAGAACAUCUGGCCAGGCAUUAACAAUUAGUAAAUUUUUUUGCAUAUGAACAGUAUUUUUCUGGUCAUGUAGAUGGGUGCACAUGACACUAAACAGCAUUGUUUAGUGUUAUCCCUCUUAACUGGUGGGUUGUAUUUGGGGUGGAGGCUGUAGCCGAGGAGAAGACAUUCACCUCUGUACUCGAGAAACUUUGUGUAGGAAUUUAGUUUAUUUUUUUAUUUUUUUUAAUUUUUUAUUUUUUACUACUUUUACUGUUAGCACAAUGCUAUAAUUGAGCUAAUCUUUGUAGUUUGGUGCAGGACCACCAAGUUUGUGUGACCCAUUACCUACUUUUUCCAUGCUCAGCCAUUACCCUGUCCUGGGGCAUCUGAGGGCAGUAAGGAACAGGUGUCCAAAGGAGGAAUGUUGGUGCCUAUGAGUAUGUUUUCCAGUUGUAUUGAAUUUCUUACUUGGUGUAUUUUUGACUUGUCUUAGUUUCUUUCCUUGUGGUCUAUGCUAUUUUACUUGCGAUUUGUUGGAUAUUCUCCCUGUCAUUAAAGAGUUGUAAAAUGGAAGUUAGUUUCUCUAUGCAAAUGCUUUAAUGGAUGAAGCUGAUAGGUUUAGCAUUGAUUUUUGCUGGUGUCCUUCAACAAGCAUGAAGGUGAUAAAUGUGUUUCCAUGGCUUUAGACUCAUUUUUGAAGUCUUGGAUUGUGUGAACAUUCUUAGAAACAAUAAAAUGUUUUAAUUAAAAGCCCUCGACUACCAGCUGAAUUCAGUGUCUACUAGGAAAAUGGGUAGAUUUGUUACAUUGUCCCUUUGCUCUCUAUGACUUUGUUCCAGUUGUCAAGGAACUUAAAUGGGUAUUCAGGAAAAAGAAUUCUUGUUUCCCUUUCCUCACCUUGCCAGUUAAAUAACUCCUGGUGACACUUCAGGUGGUAGAAUUGAAACACAAACCUGACUUCUGACCACAUGGGUCAAAGGCAAAAGGCAAAUGGCUUCAAAGCCCUUAGUGUGCUUAUCCAGUUCAGGCAGUGAGGAGAUAACCUCUGCUUUCCUCCCUGAGGAGUUUGGAGUAUUUAAGGGGGGAUGGGGGGGGUGUCACUUUGAAAAUAUGUUGCUUUUUCUCCUGAUUGUAUUGAGGCUGAUAUGGAAGGGUUAUUUCUUUCUGGCCAAUACUUUUUGGUAUUUCUAAAUAUUGCAAUCUUGAUUUUUACUAUUAAAUUUGUUAAUUGUCAGUUCUGGCUUUUUUGCAUAAAGAGUUGGUCCAUUAACUUGCCAAUUUGAAGCUUCUAACUAGAUAUUCCCUACUGAAAGUUUUGGAUUUGUUUUUAGUUUGUGGAGCAGUCUUAGCUGGGGACAGGUAAUUGACAACGGCAGAGAUACUUUCUUUUCCUAGGAUUCUAAGUCUGUAAUCCACAUCCUCAAUGUAUUCACAGGACUUUAAAAUUCUCUCCAAAUGAGGAAGGAAAUAUCCUGUUGCUUUCUAAUGUUUACUAAAAGUUGUGUUUAGAACAACAGAUUUUAAUAGGCAUCUUCCUUUGUUAUGUGUCAUUAGCCCUUUGCCCGUUUACCUUAGGGCUCUUUGAAGGAGAAAUGGAUGGGAGAAAACCUGUCACUUGGCGAAAGUAAAAGGGAUAAUUAACUGGCUCAGAGCUUAUGUGCAGAGUUCCAAGCCCCAAAGUUAAUCUAGAACCACUCGAUAACACCAAUAAAAAUAUUUAUUUCACAUCUGUUAUAUAUCUGGAAAAUGUUCUAAGCAUCUUACACAUAUUUCUCAUUAAAUCCACAGGUGACCAUUGUGAGGUAGAUAUUUUGUUCUAAUUUUCCAGAUGAGGAAGCUGAGACCCUAAAAGGUUAGGUGACAGGUUAUACAACUUGGAGUGUGGGAGGAGGAGAGAGGAACCUGAACAGGGCAAGUUGGGGAUCUGACUUUUGUUUGGGUAGAUGUAGGCACAUUGUAUUUUUGGCUUAGAUGCUUUAUUCAUCAUGGCUGAAGGUAAUACCAUUUACUCACUCACCGAAAAUUGUUUACAAUAAUCUAGAUGAAUUUGCUGUCUUUGGACAUCUGUCUUUUGACUGGACCCCAGUAUAUAGUCUGUGGAAGCUCACUUAAGGAGAGAGCUCCUUUUUGUUUGGUUAGAGAAAUUUUCUGUCCUAAAAGUAGAAAUAGCCCCUUCUAGGUAAGGAUGGAGCAUUUGAUCAUACUGGUUUCAUUAUAUUCCUCUAACAGUUGGAACCGAUUGUUUUUGAGUACUUGUUUCAAACUUCUGAGUAUUUUCCUUCUGGAAAAUAGCUCAGUGUUUAAAAUUUACAUGAACUUAAAAGGUUAAUUUUUUUUUAAAGAAUGUUUGAGGAGCAAUCAAUUCUGAUUUUGUCUUAUGGAUAGAAAUAGAAUUAGCCAUUUUCCUCAAGAAAAGUGAUUCUUCUGAAUCUUAGCUUUUCAGUAAUGAGAACUGGACUGUUUCCACUUGACCUCUAUUUCCUGUUAGUGGGAAACCGCUUCCCAGAGGUGCUGUGUGAAAGAUUGCUGGGGAAAGGGUUUCUAGAUCCCAGCAUAACAAGUUCAAGAGUCCAGCGAUAUUGUCAUUAGAAUAAUGGUCUUCAUUAAGUACUAGUUUUCAUAAUCCUGAAGCUUCAUUUUCACCAAUUUGAAAGGCAGCUAGGGAGGAGAAGACUAUGCAGGGAAGGAGGAAAACUCUGGAGUGCAUCACAGAGACCUUGAGUGAGUUAAGGCAGGGAAGAAGCAGAUUUGCUAUCCACUGAAUGAAAAUAAGAAGAAUUCCAUUGUCCAAGGUCAGAGCAAGAACACAAAGGUUUUAGUUUACUUAGUUAAUUCCUUAGGUUUGGACAUUACAGGAGACAUGGGGGUGACCAUAGCAAUUUAGCUGAUAAAUGUAUCAGAAACUCUUUCAUCAUUUUCUGUCCCCUCCUAUCUUAGGCUGACCGGUUCCCUGAUGUGUUACCUGCUUCUGCUACUGAUCCAAACUGCAGAACUUCUCAUUCAUCCCCAAGGCCUCCAGGCAGUAUCCAAUGGGGAAUCAGCUCUAAAAGGAACCAGACCAACGUUUUCCAGCCCCUUCAUUCUGUAGCUUCCCUCUGUGUGAGGAAAGGAUAGAAAUGUUCAGGACAUCAUCAUACAGGCUCCUCAUCUACAAAGUUCCAGUAGCAGUGACGCCUACACGGAAGACUUGGAACUGCAAACAGGCUGGGGUCACCUCAGUGACAUCUGACGCUGUCCAACCAGAAGUUCGAUUUUUGUUCUGGGGGUGAAGGAGGAAACAGACUGUACUAAAGGACUAAAAUAAUUUGUCUAUACUA